AUCUACCUUAUCUGGUCGGUCAUCUCUGUAACCUCCCUACCAAGGACUAAUUGGUCUUUAAAACUCCUCAAUGCACCGGGCGCGGUGGCUCACGCCUGUAAUCCCAGCACUUUGGGAGGCCGAGGCGGGCAGAUCACGAGGUCAGGAAAUCGAGACCAUCUUGGCUAACAAGAAACAAUCAGCUAUGCCUUGGGAUCAAGAUCCAGAACAAUCAACUGGAAAUUACAGUGAAGAUGAACAAAAUGGAAAGCAGAAAUGGAGAGAAGAAGGAGAAGCAGGCAGAAAGAGAGAACGAGAAAAAGAAGAAAAAAACGAAAAGGAGCUGCAAGAUGAACAGGAAAACAAAAGGAAAAGGGAAAAUGAGAAACAGAAACAGUAUCCCGAGAAAAGAUUAGUCAGCAAAUCCCUCAUGCAUACUCUCUGGGCAAAGUUUAAGUUAAACAGGUGCCCCACUAUACAAGAGAGUCUAUCACUGUCAUUUGAAUUUGACAUGACACAUAAACAGAUAAGUCAAUGGUUUUGUAAAACGAGGAAGAAAUAUAAUAAAGAAAUGUCCAAGAGAAAGCAUAAGAAAAAACAUAUGAGAUGGAGAUCUCUGUGUUGCCAAGGCUGGUCUCGAACUCCUGCCCUCAAGUGAUCUUCCUAUUUUGGCCUCCAGAAAUGCUGUGAUUACAAGCAUGAGCCAUCGCACUGGCUAAGACAUUUUACAUGACACCAUUCUCACCAAUAAAUGGAGUUCUGAAAGGAUAAACAAGAAAACAUUAACAGUCGUUGAUUCCGUGGAGUAGAACUAAAUGAGGGGUAUGCAAAGGAGUUUUUAUGUGUUUUAUUUUUACCCUACUGUAGAUUUAAAGUUUUUAUAAUGGAUGUUAAUUGAUUUUAUUUAAGAAAAAAAAUCGAGUCAAGG